AGAGGCGCGAGGGCCGGCGGAGUUUCUUCAGAGGAACUACCGCCCUGGGAGGAAGCGUCUGUUUAGUUUCAACACAGACGACUGGGCUUGGGAGCCUACGAGGUUGCAGUCUGGAGGGCGCCAACAGCAGCUACCAGGGCUGCUUUUCCUGAACACGCUGCAAGCACGUCAAGGUAGUCGGAGUCCCCUAACAAUGGAUAAAUUCGUCAUUCGAACGCCUAGAAUCCAGAAUAGCCCUCAGAAGAAAGAUUCUGGAGGAAAGGUUUACAAGCAGGCCACGAUUGAAUCUCUGAAGAGAGUUGUGGUUGUAGAAGACAUAAAAAGAUGGAAAACUAUGCUGGAGCUUCCUGAUCAAACCAAAGAGAAUCUUGUUGAAGCCUUACAAGAAUUAAAGAAGAAAAUACCCUCCAGGGAAGUGUUAAAAUCAACAAGGAUAGGUCACACUGUGAACAAGAUGCGUAAACACUCAGAUUCAGAAGUGGCUUCUCUUGCCAGAGAAGUUUACACUGAGUGGAAAACUUUCACUGAAAAACAUUCAAAUAGACCUUCUAUUGAAGUUAGAAGUGAUCCCAAAACCGAGUCGUUGAGGAAAAAUGCUCAGAAAUUACUCUCAGAAGCCUUGGAAUUAAAGAUGGAUCACCUACUGGUUGAAAAUAUUGAACGGGAAACGUUUCAUCUCUGCUCCCGCCUCAUUAAUGGGCCGUACCGGCGGACGGUGAGAGCCCUGGUCUUCACAUUAAAGCACCGAGCUGAAAUCCGGGCUCAGGUGAAGAGCGGCUCGCUGCCAGUCGGCACGUUUGUACAGACCCACAAAAAGUGACCUGAGGACGGUUCCAGCCCUGGGCCAGGCAGAGAGGAAAAUGGGCCUGUCUCUGCCGUUCAAAGACGCUUUUGAGUUUGGGUGAUGGCUGAUGCUGGCUGUGCUAGAUUUUCCCAUGGUGCCGUUCCUUUGCAGACAGAGGAUUCGGAGAGCCCUAGGAGACAGGCCUGCAGGAAUGUGCUUCAUUAGCUGCAGUGCGCUGGUGCUGCCUAACAGAACGCACACUGGCUGUCACUAGGAAGCGCCAUACGGUUGCUAUCACCCAACAUGGUGAAAGGGUGAUGGAUUUCACUGUGAAUAUGCCAAGGACACCUCUAAACUUCCCCCAUGUCAGUCAGAUGAAGUUACUACUAUAUUUCACCACCCUGCAGGUAACUGAAACUCAAUUACCGCUGCCGCUCACUCGGUUCCAUCCCCCUGAGUUUAGAUAGCUCUGGUGCCUCUCAGAACUCCCCUGUCUGUUCUCUUUGCUCUAUCCCAGGGGUGAGCCUGCGAGAGCCAGCCAACUACCCCUUCUUCCCAGAGCUCACUUAUCUGAACGUUUCAGCUCUCCCUGGAAGACCUUCUGCGUUGGUCUCCAGAGCCCCCAUGCUGAGGCUACUAAUGAGGAACUGGCCCGAAGCCUCCCACACCUCAGGGUUUAUUUGAAUACGCUGGCGCUCUCAGUUUAGGGCUCUGUAGAAGAUACAUAAUGAAAUUUCUCUUGAAAUGAAUUACUGCAGUAGAAAAAAGUACAUACAUAUAUAUGUUAAAAUGAAAUAUCUCUACACAGGCCUGUUUUAACAAUUACGUAAAUAAUACUUGUUUUUUUAAAAGUAAUAGUAAGCUGGGAACUUUUUUUUCUAAAACAAAAGGUGGAGUUCGUUCACUGAAAAGUGUUUUGAGUUGAGAAGGGGUACAGUUGGUGAAAUUUAAAAAUGAUGGAACAAGGAUUUGAGGAAUGUAGAAGACUCAAGGAAGUGGGGAUUAGAUUAGGGGAGACUGGAGCACGUUUGUAAUCUGAAAGGAAAGAGCUGGUAGAAGGGGAGAGAUUUAAAAUCCAAAAAAAAGGAAGAUGAGUUGAAAAGCAAGGGGAGAAGGGACGGGACUAACAUUAUUGCCUACCUUCUAAAUACUAGGCACUUUUCCUAAGACAGUUUAUUAACCUUUACCUGGAUCUUUAUAUAGUUUUGUAAAAAUAUUGCUUACUUCUCUCACCCAUUGUAUUAAGUAGGUAUUGUUGUUUUCAUUUUUUAGAUUUAUUCGUUUAUUUAGCAACCAUUUCCUGAGCAUCCAUUCUGUGGGGUAGGUGUAUACUGAGCAGUAGUUACAAAUGGGAGCCUGAGGCUCACUGAACAGAAACAUCACCUUCAAUUUCCUACUGCUAGUAACUAUUGGAGCUAGAAUAAUAAUAAUCGAGCGUUUACCCUGGGCCCAGCACUGUGGUAACCAUUUUACAAAAAGAAAAUACCCAGUUAAACAUGAGAAAAGUGAGGCUCAGAAAGGUAUAGUAACUUACUCAAGGUCACGCAGAUAGUGAAUGACAGAUCUAAGAUUCAAAAUCCGGGUCUAUUUGAUUGUAUAUGGUUGCCUUGGAUGAUUUCAUCUACUCUCAUGUUUUCAAGCAUCAUUUACAUGCUGAUGACAUUCCAGUUUGUAUCGUCAGCCCAGACCUGUCCCCUGACUUUCAGAUGAUAUUUCCUAGAUGCCCCAUAGACAUCUCAGAUAUAACAUGUCUUCUUUCCAUUGGCAGUACCAGCAAGCCAGACACUCCAGCUAGGAACUCAAGGAGUCAGCCUAGACCCCACAUCUCCCACCCUCAGCCAACCAAGUCCUGGUGGUUUGAUUAGGUUGGUGCAAAAGUAAUUGUGGUUUUUGCCAUUACUUCUAAUAUAUUACUUCUUUGCAUUUGCUGUUCCAGUUGCAAUGCUCUUUCCCCAGACAUCUGCAUGUUCUUGUCCUCACUUGCUUUAGGUCUCUCUUUCCCUUAUCAAAAAGGCUUUUGCUGACUAUCCUAAAUACAAUAGCACUCCCUCCCAACUAUUCUUUAAUGCUGUACCUAGCUUUAUUUUUCUUCAGAAUAUUUAUUACUCUUUAACAUAGUUAUUUCUUUAUUGUCUAUCUCCCCACUCCCAGAAUGUAAGCUUCAUGAAAGCAGAGUCUCUGUUCUGUUCCCUGUUAUAUCUCCAGCAUCUGGAACAGAGCCUGGGACAAGCUAGGUCUCCAUAACUAUUUAUUGGAUAGUUGAGUGACUGGUUGUGGAUGUACAGUAUAAGCAUCUAAUUCAAUCAGGGAGUGCUUCCUGGAGGAGCUGAUACCUGUGUUCAGUCUUAAAGGGCAGGAGUUUGGAUAGGGGAAUGUUAGUUAAUAGAAUGAAAAUUUCAAAAUUAAAGGGCAGGAGUAAUUAAUUGGGUGGUUGAGAUGCAUGCCUGGCAGAGCAAGCAGAGUAUGGAAAAACCCAGAAGUGGAGAUAUCUGGAAGGUGAUUGGUAUGGCUGGAGUAGAGGACACUGGCAGGAGAGUAGCUGGAGAUGAGGCAGGAGAGGAAGGCAAGGACCAGGAUCAGGUUUGAAGGGUCUUGAGCAUCAGGUGAAGGCGUUAGACUGAUUUGAAGCAGGAACUGGUCACUUUUGUGUUAAUAGGCUAUGUGGAAGAGAAGCUGGGGUAGGGAGACAGGAAGUAGCAAGCUUCAUGUUUAAAGAACCAAAGAGUUCUGCUAACUUAGGAACCCAGAGUAAGUUGAAAACAAAUUGCUCUCUGGCUGAAAGCCUUCAGUGGUGAUAGUUGGAAAGUAGAAUGAUUGCAGAGAUGUGCUUUGGAGAUUUGGAAAGCAGGCUGUGUUAUUUGUGGCUGUUUUCUCCUUGAUGCAUGUGCAGAAUUUCCAUGAACGCUAAUGGAGCUAUUCUGAGCAUUUGCUGAAGGGAAGGAAGCUUGCAGACAUCCCUCCCAAUCUUGCCCACACACUGAGAAGUAACUCGGAGCUACAGUCUGUUAAAAAUGAAAAGGUUGAGGCCGGGUGCAUUGGUUCAUGCCUAUAAUCCCAGCGCUUUGGGAGGUCGAGGCAGGCAGAUCACCUGAGGUCAGGAGUUUGAAACCAGCCUGGCCAACAUGGCGAAACCCUGUCUGUACUAAAAAUACAAAAAUUAGCCAGAUAUGAUGGCAGGCGCCUGUAAUCCCAGCUACUUGGAAGGCUGAGGUAUGAGAAUCGCUUGAACCUGGGAGAUGGAGGCUGCAGUAAGCCAAGAUUGUACCACUGCACUCCAGCCUGGGCAACAGAGUGAGACUCUGUCUCAAAAAAAAAAAAAAAAAGAGAAAAAGAAAAAAGUUGCCCCUGAAAUGGGGUGAGAGUAGUUCCUGAGACCUCUGAGUUACCUGUAAGUCAAGGUGUGAAUAUGUCUUAUAAGCAAGUUCAGUUGCUAGGGGAAAUGUGGGAAAGUAAAUACCAUUUGUGUCUGCUCUAAUAGCUUAUUGAUGCUUUUCUUGUAGUGGUUAAUUUGGAGGUCCUGGUUGGGCAUGGUAGCUCACACCUAUAAUCCCAGCACUUUGGGAGGCUGAGGCAGGCGGAUCACUUGAGGUCAGGAGUUUGAGACCAACCUGGCCAACAUGGUGAAACCUUGCCUGUACUAAAAAUACAAAAAUUAGCCAGAUCUGGUGGCAGGCACCUGUAAUCCCAGCACUCGAUAAGCUGAGGCAGGAGAAUUGCUUGAACCCGGGAGGCGGAGGUUGCAGUGAGCUGAGAUGGCGCCAUUGCACUCCAGCCUGGGCGACAGAGCAAGACUCACCUCAGUCUCAAAGAUAAAAUAAAAUAAAAAUAAAUAAAUAAAAAUUGGAGGUCUUGGUCCUCUGUGUAGGGACUCAGUCUCUGUAUUUUCAUUCAUUCAUUCAACAAACAAAUAUUGCCCAUCUUCUGUGUGCCAAGGACUAGACUGGCACUGGGGACACAGCAAUAAAGGAGAGAUAAUUUCCUCUGAGUCUGGUGAGGCAGAUAGACACAUAACUAAAUAAAUAGAGUAUAGCAUAUUGGGUGAUAACUAUAGACAUGAAAAUAUUGAGAAGAUGGGGAAAGGAAUGAAUAACACCACUCAGAGGAAGAAUCUUCACAGAGGAGUUCAUGUUUGAACCAAAGCCAGAAGGAUAGGUAGGAGUUCUUAGCAGAGGGCUCAGUCUAUGUGAAAGCACAGAAGCGUGAGGUGUAUGGCUAGUUUCAGUAAAGGCAAAUAAUAUGAGGUGGCUGAAGCAUAAGGUUCUUAGGAAUGGUAGUGAGAAAUUGGGCAAAAAAAGUAACCAAGGCCUUGGAGGCCUUAUCAACGAGUUUGGACUUUGGCCUUCAGAUAAUGGGAUACCAUGGGAAGUUUUUGAGGAGGUGAGGGACCUAAUCAGAUGUGUGUUUUAAAAAGAUUUAAAAAACAAAAACAAAAACAGAUAUUUUAAGAAAAUUUUAAACAUUCAAAAGAAACCCAACAAUUUAAGGCAAAGGAAAGAAACACUUGAGAUUCAGUCAAUUAGAGGUUUUUUUUUUUUGACAAAUGAAGUUUAAAGUUGCCCAAACAGAUAUCAUUAGAGAAUCCCAGGUUUGAAAAAUGGCAGGAGACCCAGAUAAUGCAUUUACUGUGUUCUGUGGUGAAGGAACAGGUAGCUGGCCUUUUUCAUUUAUAGAAUAUCAGGUUCUUAAACUUGUGCCUGUCAACCUUGGUUUUCUUUUGCUGUAGCCUCAGGCCUCAGAACCUUACUCUGAGAUUGGUAAUGUGUUUUGAAUGUGUUUAUCACAGCCAGAUGGGGCAAAGGCUCAGUUUGUUACUGCCCAUUAUUGCAAGGGAAGGGAGUCCAUCCAGAAAACAAAGCUUUGGGAGUUUCAGUUAGUUGGGUGACACUACCCUGGUAUCAAAGGAAAGAUGGUUUGAUUGGAUGACAUUGUAUUUUCUUUAAAUCAAUCAAAAUGAUACAAUUACUGUCAGGGAUGGACUUACUCAUAACCUGGGGAGGUUGGUUUCAAGAUCCAAGAAGAUCAAGACAUCCAAUCAAAUGCUGGUUUUUAAUGUUGAUAAAAUCAUUCUUUCAAUACAUAUUUGUUGAGUUCUUACGUGUCAGGUAUUAGGGUCACAGGGAUAGAGAAGACAUAAUCUUUGGCCUCAAGAAGCUUACAGUCUAGUGAAGACUGUAAACAGACAAUAAACAGACAAUUUUUACUAUUUAUUUUUAUUUUGGGAGGGGGUCAGGGUCUCACUCUGUCGCCCAGGGUGCAGUACAGUGGUGCAAUUACAGCUCACUGCAGCUUUGACCUCCCAGGUUCAAGCAAGCCUCCUACCUCAAGCCUCCCAAGUGUCUGGGACCAUAGGUAUGUGCCAUCAUACCUGGCUGAUUUUUUAUUAGCCAGAUUGUCACCAUGUUGAUCAGGCUUGUCUUGGACUCCUGGCCUCAAGUGAGCCUCCUGCCUUGGCCUUCCAAAGUGUUGGGAUUACAGGCAUGAGUCACUUUGCCUUGCCCAGACCAUUUUUGAAAACACAAAUGGGCAGGGUGCAGUGAGAUUUUUAGGGGCCAAUGGUCUGGGAUGUGGCAGGGACAUUCUCUUGAAAGUAAAAGACAAUUAUUGCAUCUCACUCCAACCAUUAAGAAGGAAGCACAAUGCCUGGGAGCCCUCUUUAGGUUUUGGAGACAGCAUAUCCCACACCUAGGAAUAUGCUCCAUCCAUGUACCGGAUGACACAGAAAGUUGUGUUUUGAUUGGGGCCCAGAGCAGGAAAGGGCUCAGCAGAAGCUCCAGGCUACAACACAAGUGGCCAUGCGGUGUGGGACAGAUGAGCUGGCAGAGCCCAAAGUACCCGAGGUAUCUGUGGUGGGAACAGAUGCCUGUGAAGUUUAUGACAAGACCCUACAGGAGAAUCACAAUGUAGACACCUGGGGUUCUGGAGCAGGGCCAUGCCAUCUGUAGCCAAGAAUUUUAUACUUCUUAAGAAACAACUCUUGAUGCUACAGGGUUCUGGUAGAGACAGAUCAUCAGACCAUGGAUCAUCAAGUUGACCAUGUGACCAAAGCUGUUCAUCAUGAGCUGGAUUCUGCCAUAUCCACCAAGUCAUAAGGUCAGGCAAAGCCAGCAGCAAUUCCUAAGAUAGAAAUAAUACAACUGGGGUUGGGCAUAGCAGGGCCAGAGGGCAGAAGAUAGUUACGUGAGCAGGUGGCCCAGACAUCUAUGUCAUCCACUACCUUUGCACCAGUACCUGCCUGUUCCUCAUUUCACACCUUUGGCUGCCUGGGGAGCUCUUUAUAAUAUCCAGCUGAUAGAAGAGAAAAAAAGCCAUGCCUUAUCCUUAGAUAGGUCAGCUCAGUGUGUGUGAGCAAGACAAAAAAAGACCGUGGCUGCACUGCAGCCCCACACAGGGGCAUCCUUGAAAGACAGCAGAGUGGGGAGUCCUUCUAGUGGGCAUAGGUUGUGCAUCAUGCACCUAGCCAUCCACUGUAUGUGGAAAGAGAAGGAGCCUGAGCUUAGACUAUACAUGGAUCUCAUGGGCAGUGGUGAAUGGCUUGGCUGGUUGGUAAGGGGUCUGAAAGGAAUAAGAUUGGAAAAUUGGAAACAAGGAGACCUGUGGUGGAGGCAUGUAGUUGGACCUAUAGGAGUGGGCACCAAGUGUGAAGAUCAUUGUAUUCCAUGUAAACACCCACCAGAGAGCACAUACCAUGGAGAAGCACUAAACAACAAUGUACACACAGUUGACAUCAACCAGUCUCUGAGGCCACCCCAGAGCUGACACAAUGGGUGUAUAAACAGCAACCAUGGUGGUGUAGUAGUCCAUUUUCACACUGCUAUAAAGAUACUACCUGAGACUGGGUAAUUUAAGAAGGAAAGAGGUUUCAUUGACUCAAAUUUCUACAUGGCUGGGGAGGCCUCAGGAAACUUACAAUCAUGGCAGAAGGCAAGGGGAAGCAGGCAUCUUCUUCACAAGACAGCAGGGGAGAGAGAGAGUGCAAAGGGGGAACUGCCAAACACUUUGAAACCAUCGGAUCUCUUGAGAAGUCACUCACUAUCAUGACAACAGCAUGGGGGAAACCGGCUCCGUGAUCCAAUCACUUCCCACCAUGUCCCUCCCUCAACACGUGGGGAUUAUAAUUCGAGUUAAGAUUUGUGUGGAGACACAGAGCCAAACCAUAUCAGAUGGUAUGGCAUGGCUCCCACUCACCAAGACUGAUCUAGCUAUUGCUGCUGCUGAGUGUUCGGCCUGCCAGUAACAGAGACCAACUCUGAACCUAGAUAUAGCUCCAUCCCUUGAGAACAACCAGCAGCCACUUGGGAAGUUGGCUAUAUUAAACCCUGUCUACCCUGGAAAGAGCUGUGAUUCAUUUUCACUGGCAUAGAUGUAUAUUCCAGAUACGAGUUCAUCUUCACUGCUUGUAGAGCUUCAUCCAGCACAACUCUCAAAGGGCUUAUAGAAUGUUUAAUCUACUGGGAUAGAUUAUGGGAUCUAUAGAUUAUGGGAUAGUCAUACAGGAUCCCAUAUGAUUCCACAGCAAAGGAGGUGCAGCAGUGGGCACAUGGUGACAGGGUCCACUUGUCCUUUCAUCUACUGCGCUAUCCUGAAGCUGCCAGCUUGCAACUGUGUCGAAGGCACAGCUGGGGCACCAGCUCAGAAACCCUGAGAGAAGAGCUGCCAUCCUCCAGGGUGCAGCACAUGUUCGAAAUCAAAGACCGUUACGUGAUGCUUUGUCUCCAAUAGGUAGAAUACAUGAGUCCAGGAACCAAGAAAUGAAAGCAGGAGUGCUCUCACUCUUACCAUCACUUCUAGUGACCCACUUGGAGUGCCUCCUGUUCUCAUAGUUCUGGGCUCUGCAGGUUUAGAGGUUUUGAGUCACAAAGGAGGAACACUUCCACUAAAAGAAACAUCAAGAUUACUAUGAACUAUUAGCUGUGACUGCACCCGGGCACUUGAGCUCCUCAUAUCAGGAGACUACUAGGCAAGAACAGUCACCAUUCUUUGAGGGAUAAUUAAUCCUGAUCAUCAGGAGGAGGUACAGCUGCUGUUAAGCAAUGGAGGGAAGGGAGGUAUAUCUUUGGUACUCAGUUGAUUCACGUGGAGACUUCUUGGUAUUCCUUUGCCCAAUUUUUUUUUCUUUUUCUUUUUCAGAGGUGGAGUCUCUGUCACCCAGGCUGGAGUGCAGUGGCACCAUCUCGGCUCACUGCAACCUCUGCCUCCUGGGUUCAAGCUAUUCUCCUGCCUCAGCCUCCCGAGUAACUGGGAUUACAGGCAUGUGCCACCAUGCCCAGCUGAUUUUUGUAUUUUUAGUAGAGAUGGAGUUUCGCCAUGUUGGCCAGACUAGUUUUGAACUUCUGGCCUCAAGCAGUCCACCUGCCUCAGCUUCCCAAAGUGCUGGGAUUACAGGCGUGAGCCACUGCGCCUGGCCCCUUGCCCAAUAUUUAUAAAAUAAUUAUACAAGUGCCCAGACCGUGACCUGAGCAGGAUAUGCUGACUUCAGGCUCAGCCCCCUCAGGGCUGAGGGUCUAAAUCAUGCCUCCGUGGAAGUGACGGAGACCGGAACACGUGCUGGCUGAGGGUAAGGAGGAUCUAGAAUGGAUAGUAGAAGAGGGAGAUGAUGAGUAUCAGUUGUGGCCUCAAGACCAGUCAGUGAUGGAGGUUGUAGUUUGUCCAACUUACUUUCCUAAGUUUCCCCCAGGAAAGGAGGUCCACCAGAACUUAAACCAAAAAGUAGAGCUGAGCAGCACAAAUGUGGGCUGUAGUGGACACCAUCCUGUGCUGCCCAGACCCCCCAGCCACCAUGCUUCCUGGGCCUCUUCCCACAGCUACUGGGAGUGCUCUCAGCCAGCAGCCUUCAGCUGUCAGCCCCCUGGGAAUUUUCCUCAAUGGAAGAGUUACCUCACUGACAUACCCCUUUCCCAGGCAGGUCAGUUCAAGGUUAUGAAGGCCUGGCCCCACUGCCUCAACUUGACAACUUGGAAGGGCCAUCUCAGCUUCAAGACCCUCCCAUGAGACUGGCUGAGGUCUUCAUACAGCAUCGGAGCCCAAUUUAUCUCUCUGAGCAAUCCUGCUUCCUUUCCUGCCCCCUUCCCAAGAGCAAUCCCUGAUAAACUUCCCGCAUGCUAAUCUCCAUCUCAGAGUCUACUUUCCAAGGAAGUGGGCCUAUAACAUAGCUCUUCCAGUUUUUGUUAACAAUUCUAGAACAGGGGUCAGCAAACUUUUUUUUUUUUUCGAGACGGAGUCUCACUCCGUCACCAGGCUGGAGUGCAGUGGCGCGAUCUUGGCUCACUGCAACCUCUGCCUCCCGGGUUCAAGCGAUUCUCCUGCCUCAGCCUCCCGAGUAGCUGGGACUACCAUGCCACCACACCCAGCUAAUUUUUUUAUUUUUAGAGAGAUUGGGUUUCACCAUGUUGGCCAGGAUGGUCUUGAUCUCUUGACCUCGUGAUCCGCGCUCCUCGGCCUCCCAAAGUGCUGGGAUUAUAGACAUGAAUCACCACACCCGGCCAGCAAACUUUUUUAAAGGAACAGAUAGUAAAUAUUUUAAGCUUUGUGAGCCACAUGGUCUCUGUCACAACUAUUCAGCUCUGCUAUUGUAAUACAAAAGCAGCUGUGGACAGUAUGUAAAUGAAUGAAUGUGGCUGUGUUCCAAUAAAACUUUAUUUACAAAAA